CGUCCGCGCGCCGAGGGGCGCGGCAGAUCUGCGGAGAGAGGACCUGCGGGGCGCGGCCGGUCCCCUCGGAGGCCUGUUCCGUCACACACUGGCGUCCUGCCUCCUCCGUAGGCGGGAGAGGUGGUCUGGAGCCCCUUCGUGCCUCAGUUUCCUCAUGGGGUAACACGAUCCUGACUCCCAGGAACCUGGCUCCUGGAGGCAGGUGACAGCCAGGGCCGCCAGAGGCCUCAGGCAGAGGGAUCCUGGCGCCCCACUCCCCACGCGUCCACAGUCGCCCGCUUCCCGGGUGCACACGACGCUCUGGGGAGGCUGGGCCCGCGCCCGGGUCACUGAGAGGAAGGGCGGACCCCAGGCUCAGGAGCACAGGGGCGAGGCCCGAGAAGGGCCUGAGCGGUUAUGGGGUGGGCGCAGAGUGAAGGGCAGAGCCUUGUGUAUCUGUGUGUGUGUGUGAGCAUGUAAGCCUGUGUGUGUGUGCGUGGGUGUGUGGGGGGGUGUUCGAGGGUGCCAUGGGGGAGGGGAGGAAGAGCCUUCCAGGCAGUGCAGACGGUAAGUGCGUAGGCCCAGUGCAGGGUUGUGUAUGUGCAACUGGAUAGGAGAUGGAGAGAGACAGGUGAGUGGUGAGGGUCCGAUCGUGUGGGAGCUUUGGGGAACUUCCAAGACUUUGGUUUUUACUGUUGCUGAGGCUGGGAGCUGUAGCAGCUGCUGGUGUCACUUUACAAGGCCCACCCCUGUGCUGAGGACCUACCGUGGGUGUGCACGGGAGCGGCAGACGGAGAUGAGUUAAGGGGUUAGCGUAGCCACGCAGCGAGAGAUGCCAGAGGCUGGGACCAGGGUGGGGGCAGAAGAGACCGUGGCAGGGGCUAGAUUCUGGAGGAAUCUGAAGGCCUAUGGCAUUGUGUGGAAGGCAGUGGACCGGAGGACUGGUGAGGUCGUGGCCAUCAAGAAAAUCUUUGAUGCUUUUAGGGAUAAGACAGAUGCCCAGAGAACAUUCCGGGAAAUCACGCUCCUCCAGGAGUUUGGGGACCAUCCCAACAUCAUCAGCCUCCUUGACGUGAUCCGGGCAGAGAACGACAGGGACAUUUACCUGGUGUUUGAGUUUAUGGACACUGACCUGAACGCAGUCAUCCGGAAGGGCGGCCUGCUGCAGGACGUCCACGUGCGCUCCAUCUUCUACCAGCUCCUGCGGGCCACCCGGUUCCUCCACUCGGGGCACGUUGUGCACCGGGACCAGAAGCCGUCCAAUGUGCUCCUGGAUGCCAACUGCACAGUGAAGCUGUGUGACUUUGGCCUGGCCCGCUCCCUGGGCGACCUCCCCGAGGGGCCUGAGGACCAGGCCGUGACAGAGUACGUGGCCACACGCUGGUACCGAGCACCGGAGGUGCUGCUCUCUUCGCACCGAUACACCCUUGGGGUGGACAUGUGGAGUCUGGGCUGUAUCCUGGGGGAGAUGCUGCGGGGGAGACCCCUGUUCCCCGGCACGUCCACCCUCCACCAGCUGGAGCUGAUCCUGGAGACCAUCCCACCGCCAUCUGAGGAGGACCUCCUGGCUCUCGGCUCAGGCUGCCGUGCCUCUGUGCUGCACCAGCUGGGGUCCCGGCCACGACAGACGCUGGAUGCCCUCCUACCGCCAGACACCUCCCCAGAGGCCUUGGACCUCCUUAGGCGACUCCUGGUGUUCGCCCCGGACAAGCGGUUAAGCGCGACCCAGGCACUGCAGCACCCCUACGUGCAGAGGUUCCACUGCCCCAGCGACGAGUGGGCACGAGAGGCAGAUGUGCGGCCCCGGGCACACGAAGGGGUCCAGCUCUCUGUGCCUGAGUACCGCAGCCGCGUCUAUCAGAUGAUCCUGGAGUGUGGAGGCAGCAGCGGCACCUCGAGAGAGAAGGGCCCGGAGGGUGUCUCCCCAAGCCAGGCACACCUGCACAAACCCAGAGCCGACCCUCAGCUGCCUUCUAGGACACCUGUGCAGGGUCCCAGACCCAGGCCCCAGAGCAGCCCAGGCCAUGACCCUGCCGAGCACGAGUCCCCCCGUGCAGCCAAGAACGUUCCCAGGCAGAACUCCGCUCCCCUGCUCCAAACUGCUCUCCUAGGGAAUGGGGAAAGGCCCCCUGGGGCGAAGGAAGCGCCCCCCUUGACACUCUCGCUGGUGAAGCCAAGCGGGAGGGGAGCUGCGCCCUCCCUGACCUCCCAGGCUGCGGCUCAGGUGGCCAACCAGGCCCUGAUCCGGGGUGACUGGAACCGGGGCGGUGGGGUGAGGGUGGCCAGCGUACAACAGGUAAGCCCGGCCCAGUCUGCCCCCGUCCCCUCAUCCUCCUUUCCCCUUUCCCCUUCCCCCCUGCUUUUCCCUCCCUUCCCCAUGCUUCCCAUUGCCCCUCCAAUGUCCAGUUCAAAUCUCUCGAGGACCUCAAGGCCUCCCCUCCACUGCACCCCCUCUGAUGGCCCCUUUAUGUGACCCUCAACUGUACACAGGUCCCUCCCCGGCUUCCUCCGGAGGCCCGGCCCGGCCGGAGGAUGUUCAGCACCUCUGCCUUGCAGGGUGCCCAGGGGGGUGCCAGGGCUUUGCUUGGAGGCUACUCCCAAGCCUACGGGACUGUCUGCCACUCGGCACUGGGCCACCUGCCCCUGCUGGAGGGGCACCAUGUGUGAGCCGCCCUACUCCCUUCACCUGGCCCUCUGUUCCUGCCCCAGCCCCUUCCCCAGACCCCUCUCCAGUCUCCUGCACCCCUUAGCCCUCCCUGCUUUGCCUGGCCCGUUGAAGUUCCAGGGAGCUUGCCCGGGUCUCCUCGGGGGAGCAGAUGAGGGCCCUGCCCCCGCCCCACUGACUUCCUCCAAUAAAGUCAUGUCUGCCCCCAA